GCCUCAGCCUGAAGGACUGCUUGCCUGUGAGGAGGGUAACUCCACCUUGCCUCUAAGAAGAGCUGGGGAAAAACAUUUCUGAGGCCUGCAGACUGUCACACUUCAGGUCACUCUUGACUGGCUGCAUCAGGACCAUGUGUGACCAGCAGCAGAUCCAGUGCCGCCUGCCGCUCCAACAGUGCUGCGUCAAGGGUCCCUCCUUCUGCUCCUCUCAAUCCCCCUUUGCCCAGAGCCAAGUGGUGGUUCAAGCCCCUUGUGAGAUGCAAAUUGUGGACUGCCCUGCAUCAUGCCCAGUUCAAGUUUGCCAGGUGUCAGACCAGGCUCCAUGCCAGUCUCAGACCACACAGGUGAAGUGCCAGUCUAAGACCAAGCAGGUGAAGGGCCAGGCUCAAUGUCAGUCUAAGACCACCCAGGUGAAGGGCCAGGCUGCAUCCCAAUCUCAAACUUCCUCUGUUCAAAGCCAGGCUCCAUGCCAAUCUGAGGUGUCCUACGUGCAGUGCGAAGCGUCACAACCUGUUCAGACUUGCUUCGUAGAAUGUGCUCCAGUUUGUUAUACAGAAACUUGUUAUGUAGAAUGCCCAGUCCAGAACUAUGUACCCUGUCCAGCUCCUCAGCCUGUCCAGAUGUAUAGAGGGCGUCCUGCAGUGUGCCAGCCUCAGGGAAGAUUCUCCACCCAGUGCCAGUAUCAAGGCUCCUAUAGCAGUUGUGGCCCCCAGUUUCAGUCAAGGGCUACCUGCAACAACUACACCCCCCAGUUCCAGUUGAGGCCUUCCUACAGCAGCUGUUUCCCUCAGUAUCGGUCCCGGACUUCAUUUAGUCCCUGUGUGCCCCAGUGCCAGACCCAGGGCUCCUAUGGGAGCUUCACUGAACAGCACCGCUCUCGGAGCACCAGCAGAUGCCUUCCUCCUCCUCGGCGGCUGCAGCUUUUCCCCCGCAGCUGUUCCCCACCAAGACGUUUUGAGCCCUGCUCCAGCAGCUACCUGCCACUAAGACCCUCUGAAGGUUUCCCUAACUACUGCACCCCACCCCGCCGCUCUGAACCCAUAUAUAACAGUCGCUGUCCUCGCCGCCCCAUUUCAAGCUGCUCUCAGAGACGUGGCCCCAAGUGCCGAAUCGAGAUUUCCUCCCCGUGCUGCCCCAGGCAGGUUCCCCCACAGAGGUGUCCUGUUGAGAUUCCUCCCAUCAGACGCCGCUCCCAGAGCUGUGGCCCGCAGCCCUCCUGGGGCGCCUCCUGCCCUGAGCUGAGGCCACACGUAGAGCCACGUCCACUCCCAAGCUUCUGUCCACCACGGCGUCUUGACCAGUGUCCAGAGUCACCACUGCAGCGAUGUCCACCUCCUGCUCCACGUCCACGUCUGCGCCCAGAACCAUGCAUAAGUCUAGAACCACGCCCGCGUCCUCUACCACGACAACUUUCAGAACCUUGUUUGUAUCCAGAACCACUUCCAGCACUACGUCCAACACCGCGGCCAGUUCCCCUUCCUCGCCCAGGGCAGUGUGAGAUUCCAGAGCCACGUCCAUGCCUGCAGCCCUGUGAGCACCCAGAGCCUUGUCCACGACCAGAGCCAAUUCCCCUGCCGGCGCCCUGCCCAAGCCCGGAGCCCUGCAGGGAGACUUGGCGCAGCCCCAGCCCAUGCUGGGGCCCAAAUCCAGUUCCAUACCCAGGAGACCUAGGCUGUCAUGAGUCUAGUCCACACCGCCUAGACACCGAAGCUCCCUACUGUGGCCCAUCCAGUUACAACCAGGGGCAAGAGAGUGGUGCUGGCUGUGGGCCUGGUGAUGUGUUUCCAGAGCGGAGGGGUCAGGAUGGCCAUGGAGACCAAGGCAAUGCCUUUGCUGGAGUGAAAGGGGAAGCAAAGAGUGCUUAUUUUUAAAGGAAAGGUGACUGAGAUAACCCUCUCUCCUGCUCUGAAAAUGUUGUUCCUCCUAUUCCACAAUUUCCAGUACGCUCUUGUUUGAAUCUCUCCAAAGAUAUUCAGAGACUCCCUAUUACGAAGGUGAUGUCCAAACUCCUUUGCCUAUCAUCCAAAGAUCCACACCUGGGUCUCAGAUGCCUCUCCAGCCUCACGUGUCACUCCUCGCCCGUACGCAUCCUCGGCUCUAGCCAGACCAGUCUGGCCACUGGGCACAGCUUGGGUGUUCCCCAGGCCAUACUUUAGAUGUCCCUGCCUCCAAGCCUCUGCUCACUCUUCCCCACUCUGCCUGGACCACUUCUCUCCUCCUCCCCAGCUUCUGAAAUCCACCCCAUCUUUCAGUGCCUCUCCCUUGGAGCCUUCUUUGCUUGUUCCCACUCACAAGAACCUGUGCCGACUUCCUAGAACUCACUGCAUCCCCCGCACUACUUGGUAACUGCCUGGUGACAUCUCUUGAAUUGUUAUUUCACUUUGCAGGCAUGUCUUCCUUAUCUGCCCAACUAGGUUGUAAACUCCCAACUGAGUGGAGUCGGAGAAUCUCUAAAUCUCAGUGUCUAUCCUGGGGCUGGCUGUUGCUUAGCAAGGCUUGUGGGUUGGCAGCUUGAACCAUGUUCUGUCCUGAUGCUCAACUGCAGGAACUGAGGUGAGAGGAGGCCAUGUGACAAUAAAGAUCAUUAUGUACUCACUGC